ACAAAUCAGCCCCGUUGCUGAGUCUCCGUUUCCUCACCUCUACAAUGGGCAUCUUAACUACCCACAGAAUCUCCACUCUGGGCGCUACCCUGUGCCAGGCACCUGGUCCUGAACCUGACCCCCUGAAUCUCCUCUGCAUCCUUCCCUUUAGCCAGGGCCCUGCAUACAGUAGGGGAUCAAUAAAGAUUCAUCUCCUGCAGGAACGCUGGGUAUUGUGAUUUUCUGACUUUAAGACAAGGAAAGCAGGGCUCAGAGAUGGUUGGCUCCUGCCUGAGGCCACGCAGCUCUGUCGGGAUUUGAACCCUUGUCUGUGUGCUCCAGGGCUGACUCAUUCCUCCCUUCCUGCUGCCUCUUCAGGGGCAGUGGAGGUGGGGCUUGGAGGGUGCCCAGGGCUGUGCGGUGGAAGCGGGUGAGGGCAGAACACCUGGGCUGGCCAGCAAGGGGGCUGGAGUCCCGAAGCCAAGGCGGAGGGGAGCCCCAGGGCUGCCCCAGGCUGGGCUGCCAAGGGACUGGGGCAGGCAGGCGAAAACGAGGAGGCCGCUCGCUCACCAAGGAGAGGAGAGAAUAGGGCUGCCCAUUUUAAAUUUUAAAUUUCUUCCAGACAGAUGUCAUUGGGGAAGGAACAGUUCGUGCUUGCAGCUGCAGGAGGGGGCGGCACGGGCAGCCCUUGGUGGUCCCUUCCUCUCAGGAGCUGCAACCUGCUCAUUCUUCCUGGUGUGACACUGCCGUGGCACAAGGGCCCAGCCCUCUGCGGUUUGCAAAGCCCCUUCCCAUUCAUCGGCACUACCUCACUUCUCCAAACAGGCUGGGGGCCAGUGCGUUCCCACAUCACAGACCAGGGAUCAGAGAGGUUCGGAACAUGCCCAAGUCACACAGCACGUUGGCAAGAGAGUGGGGAUUCAAACUCUGGUCUAACCACACACCUAUCCCACUGCUUCUCCGGGGUGGUCGCGCCCCUCUUUUAGGUCAGGUCUGCACCUAAGCCACCCCAAAAUAACAAGUCCCCUCCUGCUGAGAUCUGACUUCUCCCCCUUAGCAAGAACUGUCUUAACUUCUAGACCUGUCCUCCAAGGCCAUCCCUAACCUGGCAUACUGUGCCUUCCCAUUGGUCCCUUACAGGCAGUGACUGUUUGUUAUUUGCCAACCCUGGGCCCCACACCACGCCGCUCCAUUUCCAGAUCUUUUCUGUGUCAUCUUGUUUGCUUCCCCAGCCUUACACAAACACACACACACACACACACACCCCUUCACUCAGGGACACCCUACAUAUACUCAAAAUCAAGCUCAAAUGCUGCCACCUCCUCCAGGAAGACUUCCUGAUGCCCUGUGGCUAUGUCUCUAAGUUCUAGUAGUGUUUAGCCUGUGCCACUCAGCUGCCUUGUCCUGGGCCCCUCCUGCAUCAGGAGAUCCCUUUGGACACACCCUCCUCUGGAGCCCAUCUCUGCAUCUCUCCCUGGGCCCAAGCUCCAUUCUUUCCAGGCAGCUCAGGUCAGGCAUUGAGAGCGUUUGCUGAAUGGCACUGCAUGACGCUUCGGCCAGGAAGAGCCUCAGGAGACGGCCAGCAGGCACUGGUCUGUCUCAAGGGGAGGUGCCUUCUGGGGAAUGUGUUUGAAAUGUGGCUUCAAGGCCUCCAGGCCGGGCCCCGCCUUCCUCUGCUGCUCCCUGGGGGCACAGCUUUCAGCCCCCACACAGCCCAGCUGUCUGCCCCUUGGCAUUGGAGGAAGCUCGAGGGCUGUUGCUCCAAGAGCCUGGGCCAAUAGCAAGCACCCGCUUCCCCUCCCCGCCCGUUUGGUGACCCAGCAUGUAGACAGGCUGUUCCCUGUGCCAGCUCUGGGCUUGUUUGAAGCUUCAGACAAGAGGCAAGGCCUUUCCUGUGGCCACUGUCAGAAGAAAGAGAGAACACUGCUUGCCCUGGUUCCCUUGGGCCUGCCCUCUCCUGGGCCAGCCUUCUCUCCUCCCUUGUGGCCAGGUUUGUCUCACCCACUGACAUGCUGUGUGGCCCUGGCGGCCGAGCUGCGGCUACGUGCUGUGCACCGUGCUGCUGGCCCUGGCUGUGCUGCUGGCUGUAGCUGUCACCGGUGCCGUGCUCUUCCUGAACCACGCCCACGCGCCGGGCACGGCGCCCCCACCUGUCGUCAGCACUGGGGCUGCCAGCGCCAACAGCGCCCUGGUCACUGUGGAAAGGGCGGACAGCUCGCACCUCAGCAUCCUCAUUGACCCGCGCUGCCCCGACCUCACCGACAGCUUCGCACGCCUGGAGAGCGCCCAGGCCUCGGUGCUGCAGGCGCUGACAGAGCACCAGGCCCAGCCACGGCUGGUGGGCGACCAGGAGCAGGAGCUGCUGGACACGCUGGCCGACCAGCUGCCCCGGCUGCUGGCCCGAGCCUCAGAGCUGCAGACGGAGUGCAUGGGGCUGCGGAAGGGGCAUGGCACGCUGGGCCAGGGCCUCAGCGCCCUGCAGAGUGAGCAGGGCCGCCUCAUCCAGCUUCUCUCUGAGAGCCAGGGCCACAUGGCUCACCUGGUGAACUCCGUCAGCGACAUCCUGGAUGCCCUGCAGAGGGACCGGGGGCUGGGCCGGCCCCGCAACAAGGCCGACCUUCAGAGAGCGCCUGCCCGGGGAACCCGGCCCCGGGGCUGUGCCACUGGCUCCCGGCCCCGAGACUGUCUGGACGUCCUCCUAAGCGGACAGCAGGACGAUGGCGUCUACUCUGUCUUUCCCACCCACUACCCGGCCGGCUUCCAGGUGUACUGUGACAUGCGCACGGACGGCGGCGGCUGGACGGUGUUUCAGCGCCGGGAGGACGGCUCCGUGAACUUCUUCCGGGGCUGGGAUGCGUACCGAGACGGCUUUGGCAGGCUCACCGGGGAGCACUGGCUAGGGCUCAAGAGGAUCCACGCCCUGACCACACAGGCUGCCUACGAGCUGCACGUGGACCUGGAGGACUUUGAGAAUGGCACGGCCUAUGCCCGCUACGGGAGCUUCGGCGUGGGCUUGUUCUCCGUGGACCCUGAGGAAGACGGGUACCCGCUCACCGUGGCUGACUAUUCCGGCACUGCAGGCGACUCCCUCCUGAAGCACAGCGGCAUGAGGUUCACCACCAAGGACCGUGACAGCGACCAUUCAGAGAACAACUGUGCCGCCUUCUACCGCGGUGCCUGGUGGUACCGCAACUGCCACACGUCCAACCUCAAUGGGCAGUACCUGCGCGGUGCGCACGCCUCCUAUGCCGACGGCGUGGAGUGGUCCUCCUGGACCGGCUGGCAGUACUCACUCAAGUUCUCUGAGAUGAAGAUCCGGCCGGUCCGGGAGGACCGCUAGACUGGUGCACCUUGUCCUUGGCCCUGCUGGUCCCUGUCGCCCCAUCCCCGACCCCACCUCACUCUUUCGUGAAUGUUCUCCACCCACCUGUGCCUGGCGGACCCACUCUCCAGUAGGGAGGGGCCGGGCCAUCCCUGACACGAAGCUCCCUGGGCCGGUGAAGUCACACAUCGCCUUCUCGCCGUCCCCACCCCCUCCAUUUGGCAGCUCACUGAUCUCUUGCCUCUGCUGAUGGGGGCUGGCAAACUUGACGACCCCAACUCCUGCCUGCCCCCACUGUGACUCCGGUGCUGUUUGCCGUCCCCUGGCCAGGAUGGUGGAGUCUGCCCCAGGCACCCUCUGCCCUGCCCGGCCAAAUACCCGGCAUUAUGGGGACAGAGAGCAGGGGGCAGACAGCACCCCUGGAGUCCUCCUAGCAGAUCGUGGGGAACGUCAGGUCUCUCUGAGGUCAGGUCUGAGGCCAGUAUCCUCCAGCCCUCCCAAUGCCAACCCCCACCCCGUUUCCCUGGUGCCCAGAGAACCCACCUCUCCCCCAAGGGCCUCAGCCUGGCUGUGGGCUGGGUGGCCCCAUCCUACCAGGCCCUGAGGUCAGGAUGGGGAGCUGCUGCCUUUGGGGACCCACGCUCCAAGGCUGAGACCAGUUCCCUGGAGGCCACCCACCCUGUGCCCCGGCAGGCCUGGGGUCUGCAGUCCUCUUACCUGCUGUGCCCACCUGCUCUCUGUCUCAAAUGAGGCCCAACCCAUCCCCCACCCAGCUCCCGGCCGUCCUCCUACCUGGGGCAGCUGGGGCUGCCAUCCCAUUUCUCCUGCCUCUGGAAGGUGGGUGGGGCCCUGCACCGUGGGGCUGGACUGCGCUAAUGGGAAGCUCUUGGUUUUCUGGGCUGGGGCCUAGGCAGGGCUGGGAUGAGGCUUGUACAACCCCCACCACCAAUUUCCCAGGGACUCCAGGGUCCUGAGGCCUCCCAGGAGGGCCUUGGGGGUGAUGACCCCUUCCCUGAGGUGGCUGUCUCCAUGAGGAGGCCAACCCUUGCCAUUGACCGUGGCCACCUGGACCCAGGCCAGGCCCGGCCCGGCGAGUGGUCAAGGGACAGGGACCACCUCACCGGGCAAAUGGGGUCGGGGGGACUGGGGCACCAGACCAGGCACCACCUGGACACUUUCUUGUUGAAUCCUCCCAACACCCAGCACGCUGUCAUCCCCACUCCUUGUGUGCACACAUGCAGAGGUGAGACCCGCAGGCUCCCAGGACCAGCAGCCACAAGGGCAGGGCUGGAGCCGGGUCCUCAGCUGUCUGCUCAGCAGCCCUGGACCCGCGUGCGUUACGUCAGGCCCAGAUGCAGGGCGGCUUUUCCAAGGCCUCCUGAUGGGGGGCCUCCGAAAGGGCUGGAGUCAGCCUUGGGGAGCUGCCUAGCAGCCUCUCCUCGGGCAGGAGGGGAGGUGGCUUCCUCCAAAGGACACCCGAUGGCAGGUGCCUAGGGGGUGUGGGGUUCCGUUCUCCCUUCCCCUCCCACUGAAGUUUGUGCUUAAAAAACAAUAAAUUUGACUUGGCACCACUGGGGGUUGGUGGGAGAGGCCGUGUGACCUGGCUCUCUGUCCCAGUGCCACCAGGUCAUCCACAUGCGCA